GUAAUAGCUGCACGGGUGUAAACAUGUUCAAACUUAUCGACUGGAGGCUCAGACCAGCCUGCAGAGCUGCAGCCACCCUUCAUGCCCUCCCUACCCUCCCUGCUGACGAUCAUGCUCCAGUUACUACUUGGAUUCACUUUGGCCAACAUGGUUGGAAUGUAUCUGGCUCAGAACUAUGAUGCACCAAACCUGGCUAAAAAAAAGGACUUGAUGCCGGGAAGAAAGAAACCCCCUAGUUCAUGAGGCCGACUCCAGCACUGCCUUCUGGAUACACUGAUUCCACCACUCUUGAGGGCCUCCUUUACCAUCUCAACCAAAGCCUUUUGUUUUUAUCUCCAG